AUUGCACAACGCGGAGGACUAGCCUGGGGUCACAGGGAUGCCGCGGCUCCUCCGCUUGUCCCUGCUGUGGCUUGGACUCCUGCUGGUUCGGUUUUCUCGUGAACUGAGCGACAUCAGCAGUGCCAGGAAGCUGUGCGGCAGGUACUUGGUGAAAGAAAUAGAAAAACUCUGCGGCCAUGCCAACUGGAGCCAGUUCCGUUUCGAGGAGGAAACCCCUUUCUCACGGUUGAUUGCACAGGCCUCGGAGAAGGUCGAAGCCUACAGCCCAUACCAGUUCGAAAGCCCGCAAACCGCUUCCCCGGCCCGGGGAAGAGGCACAAACCCAGUGUCUACUUCUUGGGAAGAAGCAGUAAACAGUUGGGAAAUGCAGUCACUACCUGAGUAUAAGGAUAAAAAGGGAUAUUCACCCCUUGUGUGAACUUGCCACUCCCCCAUCAAAUCUGGACAGGCUUCUGACCCUUACAACCAGUAGGACAUGGCAGAAGUUAUACUGUGCAGCUACCAAGGCUAAAUCAUAAAAGAUUUAUGCUGAGACACACUCACUUUUAAUUCUCUACUCACCACUAUGAAAGGUGACCACCCUGAAGCCACCAUAUUGUGAGGAAAUCCAGGCCACAUGUACAUGCUCCAGUUAACAGCCCAGCUAACAUCCCAGUCAAGAGCCAGCAUCAACUACCCAUCAUGUGAGUGAAGACACCUCCAGAUGAUUCCAGUCCUUUGCCUUCAAGUCACCCCUGGCUGGCAAUUCUUCCCAACUCAUGUCCUAGUAGCCAUUGUGGAGCAAAAACAAAGUCAUCCCUGGUGUGCCCUGUCUCAAUUACUGACCCAUGGUAUCUGUGAGCCUAAUAAAGUAGUUGUUUUAAAUCACUAA